AGAGCGCACCCAGCCGGCGCCGCGCAGCACUGGGACCCUGCUCGCCCUGCAGCCCAGCCAGCCUGCUCCGCAUCCCCCUGCUGGUCUGCCCGCCGACCUGCGCGCCCUCGCUGCCGCCCGUGUGCGCCCCUCGACCCCAGCGGCACCAUGCAUCUCUCCCAGCUGCUGGCCUGCGCCCUGCUGCUCACGCUGCUCUCCCUCCGGCCCUCCGAAGCCAAGCCCGGGGCGCCGCCGAAGGUCCCGCGAACCCCGCCGGCAGAGGAGCUGGCCGAGCCGCAGGCUGCGGGCGGCGGUCAGAAGAAGGGCGACAAGGCUCCCGGGGGCGGGGGCGCCAAUCUCAAGGGCGACCGGUCGCGACUGCUCCGGGACCUGCGCGUGGACACCAAGUCGCGGGCAGCGUGGGCUCGCCUUCUGCAAGAGCACCCCAACGCGCGCAAAUACAAAGGAGCCAACAAGAAGGGCUUGUCCAAGGGCUGCUUCGGCCUCAAGCUGGACCGAAUCGGCUCCAUGAGCGGCCUGGGAUGUUAGUGCGGCGCCCCCUGGCGGCGCUCAGCAGCUGCCACUGCCUGUCCCACACCUUGACUGUCCCAUCCCAGGCUACGGGCAAGCUGCUGUCUCCUCCCCAGAAACCCUUGUCAGUGUCGGAUCUUCUCCCGGAGGGAAACAAGAGCGCCUGUCCAGCACACUGUCUCUUUUUUACAGUACAGAACACUUUUUCACAGUUUGUGAACCCAUUCACCUCUCCAUAUUGAACAGCUUAAGGGCGAAGUGCUGGCCUAAGGCACUCUAGGACCCACUGCACCCCGAACAGACUCGUGGAAAUAUUUGUCAAUGACCAGAGAAACCAGCACACCCUGGCCCAUGGCCACUCCCACCUGCCCGAGGUUUUAACCAGUGCCCUUCCUCUCUUUGCAGCCAGACCUCACUCGGCUGUGGGCCUCUCCCCAGUUCUGCAAAGGCUGUAGUUGUCUGUGAUCUUGACUCUCCCCUGCACAGGGAGAAGAAUGAUUCUGACACUUGGGGACCAGCCUUCAGUAGCUACCCUUGGAAUGCCUUUGCUCUCUUCUCUCCUGUCUAAACAACAAAGAGACGGAGUCUGAGGCCUCAAAUUUUCAGUUUGAUUUAAGCAUCAAGUUCAAACUUUAGAACCUGAGCAAAUGUUAGUGACUCUCCAUUGGUUCGUACCUGGAAUGCGCAUCCCCACAGGGGCUUUGUUCUUGGGCCUGGAUGUCUGUGGUCACCAAGUGAUGGCCAAACGGGUGGUGAAAGAUGCUGUGUAGGAGGAAUCCACAUUGUUAAGAAUUCUCGACCCCUUUGAUCAGGGGGGUUCAAUAAUCUCCUACCAGCUCUCUUAGCAUAGAUGAACACUUACCGUCGACACCUUCAACACCGGCUUACGCCCAACACCAGCUGUUUUAUUAUUAUUUGGGAAGGGCGGUGUGGAUUUAUUAUUUGGGAUUUUUUAAAUGAAAAAUAAAAACCCCACCCUCACUGCCCCCCAUUCCCAGUGAGAGAGCAGAACAUCAUUCCUGCAGGCUCCUGGUGACGAUGCCCAGGAUAUAUCACUGGGCGUAAAGAGAAAGACAGCUUAGAUUUUUCACAUUAAUGAAAACUCUUUGAGGUUGUGGCUGUUUCUCCACGCAGUGGGUGACCUGGGCUCUAAGCCACCGUAAUGAUGGUGGUUGAUGGUUCUAGGUAUUCAUUGUAAAAUGCUAAUGACAGAGACUGGGUGUAGGUGAAACCUGAAUGAACACUUUGCCCCUGGGGCCCAGCAACAUCACAGACAGCUGUCAUCUGUGUAAACUCACGGCAGAGCCAGAGAAGGGAGUGGGGGAGGGUUCAUCAAGCCAUUCUGGCCCAGGUCCCCUCUGUGCAUGCUGUCCUUUGGGAGGGCACUGAACGCCCCUGAAGGCCACCUUCCUUGGGCCCCGGGGCACCCACACACCCAUUAGCAGAGAGUUUACCCUAACAACACUCAGAGCCCAUGACUGUGCAUUUCCCCAAGGCUGGUGUGAGACACCAUUUCCUCUGCUCCUGAAGGGGACCUGGACCCAGACCCUUUCCUCUGCACAACCAGCUAGGGAAGGAGGUGCUGUUUACUGGGUGGCAGCUGUGACCCAGACACUGCCGAUGCCCGAUCCGAGGCUCCCUGUUGAAUCUGAAAGCCAGCCCUAGGAGGUGGCUAUUAUCCAAUUUUAUGGGUGAACACUCCCAGCUAUCCAGGGUCAUCCAGGGACCCAACGUCAGAGUAGAGAUUUGAGCCCAGGAUUCCUGAUCCUGAGAUGUCUCUCUUCUCCUUCCAUCCAUGGUCACUCAGACACACGAACCCCGGGCGAGCACUGACUGAGGGUUUGCGUUGUAGCAAAAAAGGGAUGGGAGAUUUUCCAUUCUCUUUCUCUCACUGCGCUUCCCUGAGUGCCAAGGGCAAGGCCUGUGGUUAGACUGGGGGAAGAAGGAGUGUUGCAGACACGCUGGUUCCACUUGUACUGGGGCAGCAAAGCAGAAGGGGCCUGGGGAGUGCGCAAUGGGGGGCUCCUCCCCUCUGCAGGAAGGCCUGGUUGGGGGGGUGGCGGAGGUAGGGGAACAUCCCUCAAGCUGCUGGGAGAAGGGGAGGAAAGGUUCUAGAACCACCCUGCCUGCUAGGAUUUCUCAGCUAAGGGGCCAGAACUGAGCGUCCCGUGUUCACUCUGUGUUUCAGGAUCGGGAACUGGCUCCGUUGUGCUGAGGUCAUCUUUGGUCAUCAGCCUCCAGCAUCUGGAAACACCUCCAACGCAAUGUGGCUUUUACAUUUCUUUCUUUCUUUCUUUUUUUUUCCUGGUACUGGGAAUACACAACACCAGCUGUUUUAUUAUUAUUUGGGGAGGGGGUUGUGAUUUUAUUAUUUGUUUUUUUAAAAUGAAAAAUAAAAAGUUAUAUAUUAUAUAUAUAUUAUAUACAUGAAACACACACACCUACACCGACUUGAUGACAAGGGACAGUUUUUAAGAGACUGACAGAACCAGCUGUAAAACAUUGCUGUUUGUAAAUUCAUGUCAUGCAUAAAUGUAUUUAUGUUGUAAAGCUAUUUAUAUUGUUUAUAAAGAGAUAUUUAUAAAAAUUUUAUUUAUGUAACUAAAUGAAAGAAGUCAAUCAUUGUAAUGUUUUUGUCCUAACUAGUUAAAAAAAAUGUAAAAAAAAAAAAGUCAUUCCAUGAAUAUCUUGAAAA